AUUCCUUGCCUUUGAUGUGAGUGAUAGGAGCGGGCGAUUCUGCUUCUCCCUCCAUCUCCCGGCGGGGAUUGUACGGUGAGAGAAUGAGAGCAAAACCUCAGAGCCCCCUUCCCAGGAACCCUGUCCCAGCCUGGUCCCCACCCACCACCACCACUGACCCGAUGCUAGAGAAGGAUGCGGCUGGAGGUGACUUCCCAGCCAACUUGGUCCUCCAACUAAUGCCACUGAAGACAUUCCCAGCUGCUAUCCGGGGAGUCAUCCAGAGUGAGCUCAACUAUUCUGUGAUCCUGCAGUGGGUGGUGACAAUGGACCCUGAGCCUGUGCUGAGCUGGACCUUCAGUGGGGUGCCCUGUGGGAUGGGAGAGAAGCUGUUCAUCCGACGGUUGUCCUGUGAGCAGCUGGGCACCUACAUGUGCAUAGCCACAAACAGCAAGAAACAGCUGGUCUCUGAGCCUGUAACCAUCUCGCUGCCAAAACCCAUCAUGCAGCCCACAGAAGCAGAGCCCAUGGAGCCAGACCCCACUCUGUCCCUGUCAGGAGGCUCUGCCAUCGGGCUCCUUGCGGCUGGGAUCCUGGGAGCCGGGGCACUGAUUGCAGGCAUGUGUUUCAUCAUCAUCCAGAGCCUAAGGACUGACAGGCAGAGAAUAGGAAUAUGCAGCUGAAAUGUGGGCAACUCUCCUGUCAGCUGAAGAGAUGGGUGCUUUGUACCUCUCUAUCCACGUGGAAAAAAAAACCCAUCCCAUAGCUUCCAAGUCUACAACAUCUCUGUUCAAGGGAACAACCCAACGUAACCAGACUCCCUUUGCCCUGUUUCUGAAACACCUGAAGAAAACAUCUGAUGGGUUGACUCGGUGCCAUCCUUGGUCCCAUCGCCGUGACACGUUGUGCAAGCAAAGCAUCAGAGGCUCAUCCCUGUCUGUGGGAGCUCAGUGCUCAGAAAACAGGGGGGAGGUUUUACCUUGGAAAUUGGCCAGACCCCAAAAUAUGUCUUUUACACAUGCUGCUUUUUUUUUCUCUUUUUCAAAAAGAACCAAAAAAUAAAUUAAAACACCACCA